UGGCAGCUGGAGCUCCGGCCCGGCCCGAGGGGGAAGACUAUGGCUGUUGUCAGCAGGUCCUCCUGAGCCACAGACCUGCCUGAGGCCAGAGGGGAGAGGAGAGCCAGGGCUGGACCGAGCCCUUGGAAGCCUGGUGGGGGAGGGGGUGGUCCUAGUCAAGGAGACUCAGUGGGCACCACCCUGGAGACAGGAAGAAGCCCCAGGCCAGUGGUGACUCCAGCUGGAGAGAAUUUCACAGGAAGAGCAUGGCUGGCAGGUGGCAGGGCCCAUGGCUGCUGAGAGUCGAGAGCUCAGUUGCGGGGGGAGCGGAGGGACCUUAGGGCAGGCUCCGCCAGCCUGGCUGGCUGUUCUUUCCUGCCAAGCCCCAGCUUCACUUCUGGGGGCAGGGGCUUCCUGGCUGUGGACUUCCUUGUCCAUCCCCUGGUCAGUGCCGAGGGAGAGACGCUCACCCCUGUGCUCCUGGGACGGGCGGGAGGCCCGGACAGGCUAUGAUUCCCACGCCACCUGUGCUGGGAGAGCCCCUACUGUGUGUUCAUUCCUCACAUGAUGUACUUGCCUGGAGGAUUCCGCUCUGCACUUGGGGAGAGGGGUGAAUAAGACCCGCCCCUGGCUGCAGGGAGCUUCUGCUGUGAGCAGGAGACAGGGAGGGCUGAAGGCUGUGCAGCACCCUGGUAUGGGGUGAGUGAGGGUGCCUAGAGGGCGCCCACAGAAGGGGCUCCUGACUCGGACUGAGGGGCAGGGAGGUCUCCUUGGAUGAAGGGGUGCCUGGGCUAGGGCUGCAGGCUGGCUGGCCCUUGCCAAGAGAGGACAAGAGGGAGCCAUUCCGUGUAGAGGGCAUAGUGGCUGCAAAGGCCUCAGGGAGCUGAGGGCAUGUGGCGUGCUCUGGGUAGCACAUGACUGAGUGUGCGCCUGGACUGGGCAUCCGGGAUGGGGUCACCAAGAGCCUCGUGGACGAUGGAGAAGUUGCAAGGGGAUUUGCUGAUGGGCAGCCCUGCCCAGCAGCGACUCCACUGGGCUUGUUCCUUGUCCGUUCCUUGAACAACUUGAAGUCACAGCAGCCAGAGGAAAUUCUGCCACCAUUUUCCCAGGUCUGCAGCCCCUCCAGCUGGGAACCUGCUCCUGGAGCCAUCCCUCUGCAAACAGAGAGCCCAGAGUGCCUCGGGGAAAAUUGGCUGAAUAAAAGAGCGAUCAGGACGCCACGGCUCCGCCUGAAGCGAUGGCCCAGCCCUACCCCCCCGCCCAGUACCCCCCUCCGCCACAGAACGGCAUCCCUGCCGAGUACGCCCCGCCCCCACCGCACCCCACGCAGGACUACUCCGGCCAGACCCCGGUCCCCACAGAGCAUGGCAUGACCCUGUACACACCAGCACAGACCCACCCCGAGCAGCCAGGCUCCGAGGCCAGCACACAGCCCAUCGCCGGGACCCAGACAGUGCCGCAGACAGACGAGGCGGCACAGACGGACAGCCAGCCGCUCCACCCCUCCGACCCUACAGAGAAGCAGCAGCCCAAGCGGCUACACGUCUCCAACAUCCCCUUCCGGUUCAGGGACCCCGACUUGCGGCAAAUGUUCGGGCAAUUCGGAAAAAUUUUAGACGUGGAGAUCAUUUUUAACGAGCGGGGCUCCAAGGGUUUUGGGUUUGUAACUUUUGAAACUAGCUCAGAUGCUGACCGAGCCCGGGAGAAGCUGAAUGGGACGAUCGUAGAGGGACGGAAAAUUGAGGUCAAUAAUGCCACGGCCCGAGUGAUGACCAACAAGAAGACGGGGAACCCCUACACCAACGGCUGGAAGCUAAAUCCAGUGGUCGGCGCAGUCUACGGGCCUGAAUUCUAUGCAGUGACGGGGUUCCCCUACCCCACCACCGGCACAGCCGUUGCCUACCGGGGCGCACAUCUUCGGGGCCGGGGCCGGGCCGUGUAUAAUACAUUUCGGGCUGCGCCACCCCCACCCCCCAUCCCGACUUACGGAGCGGCACUGGAGCAAACGCUUGUUAAAAUGCCAGUCCCAUGGGCGGGGCUGGCACCGUGCCCCCUCCCUCCUCAGCAGACACCGGAGCCGGCCUACCCCACCUCUCCAGCGUUCCCACCACUUUCUUGUCCGUUUGCUUCCAGGGUCGUGUAUCAGGAUGGAUUUUAUGGUGCUGAGAUUUAUGGAGGCUACGCAGCCUACAGAUACGCUCAGCCCGCUGCAGCGGCGGCAGCCUACAGCGACAGUUACGGCAGAGUCUACGCAGCUGCCGACCCGUACCAUCACACCAUCGGGCCCGCGGCGACCUACAGCAUUGGAACCAUGUGAAACCUUCCACCGUUUCCUUCUCGGACCAUGAAGGGCAAAAACAAAAAAACAAAAAAAAUCACAAAACAAAAAAAACAAAAAAAGAUGUUAAGAUCCAAGCAACAAAAAAAAAACCAACCAAACCAAGAGGCAUCCAACCAAGUCCAAGUCCCGCGUCCUGGCCACACGCCCGCACCGAGGGAGCACGCCGGCAGGGGCGCCGAGGAGCGGCCCCAGGACAGGACGGCCCCACCGCGUCCUGGCUGGCAGCACAGUGGGAACACGCCCCUCCGUCUCAGGCAGUGGGGGAGUUGGAGGGGAAGGGGCCUCCCUUGUGGGACCCGUGGGGGGCUCUGUUUUCCAUCCAGUCUUCCUUUCCCAGCCCCCAACUCCCAAGACAGACAGUGUGGAGCCCAGCGGCGGCGGAGCAGGCCCGGGCCUGAGCAGGCAGGCGCUGCUAGCAAGACUUGAUCUUUGUGGCCAGCUGUGCCAGGGGGCCGGCGGGGCUGAGGGGUGCGGGCAGCUUUCAUCCCAGGGGCUCCACUGGGCCCCGUCACCCUCCUGUCGCGUCCCCUGCGUCCCACCUCCCUCCUGCCCGGCAGUCCCGCCCGUGCCCCCAGCCUGGCGAGGAAGCCGUCCAACAGUAGCCCCGGGGCCAGCUCCCAACAGAAAGGGCUGACGUGGCUCCAGGACUCAGGGGCGCUCCAUGGGAGGACGAAGGAAGCCCAGCCAGCCAGGAGCCACUCCUCACACCUCCAAGUGUGGCCAAGUGGGCCCUGAGGCCAAGGACUUACUUGCUCUUCCUGGCCAUCUCUCCCUUUCUGGAGGAGGCCCGGGGCCUGUGUACACCAAGGCUGACCUCGUGCUGCCUGCUGGGACCCAGCCCUCCCUGCCGCUCCCCUGUGAGCCCAGUCCACCGUGGGCGCCCAGGGCCAGGGACGGGCCAGCGCCCGGCUGCAUCGCGAGGUUGGGAGUCACAGUGGCUGUGGGCCUGGACGGGCACAGCCAGAGCAGGGGCCCAUGGGAAGGGCAAGGGAUGGGGAAGCCUGGGCCGGCCCCUUCCCUGCUCCCAAGGCAGGUGUCCAGGUGGCGGGAGCAGCACCAAGGACAGCCAGGCUUACCCGGUGGGAGGAGCAGGAGCAGAGCAGGUGGCAGGGAGGAACCCCUGGCGAGGCAGGGAGCACUGAAGUAGGGAAGCAGCAAAAAAUACAGGCUCCCAACGUGGCUCCACUGUCUCAUGAAGUGUCAAAAAUUUAAAAAUACACCUCACUUUCUAUUCAGCAUCAGCUAUUGAAAUGGAAUUCUCCUUUUCUAUUCCCGUUGUACAUAGCCCCACGCCCUGCCUCCGGCUUUGUCCUCUGUACAGAGCCCCCUGUCCCCUCUGCUGUUCCGGACCCUUUUCUUGCAGCAGCUCAACCCCCCGACUCACUCAGAUCCCCAGGACUGCAGCCGAGCCCCGGGCUUCCUUUCUUACCAUUCUGUAUGCUUCCAAGGUGUGACCAUUCAAACUAACAGUAUUAUUAAGAUUAUUAAUAAAGAUUUCUUUCUUCAAACCAGGA